AGUGGCGAUUGGAGGGUAGACCUGUGGGCACGGACGCACGCCACUUUUUCUCUGCUGAUCCAGGCAAAUGUGCAAUACCAACAUGUCUGUACCUACUGAUGGUGCUGUAACCACCUCACAGAUUCCAGCUUCGGAACAAGAGACCCUGGUUAGACCAAAGCCAUUGCUUUUGAAGUUAUUAAAGUCUGUUGGUGCACAAAAAGACACUUAUACUAUGAAAGAGGUUCUUUUUUAUCUUGGCCAGUAUAUUAUGACUAAACGAUUAUAUGAUGAGAAGCAACAACAUAUUGUAUAUUGUUCAAAUGAUCUUCUAGGAGAUUUGUUUGGCGUGCCAAGCUUCUCUGUGAAAGAGCACAGGAAAAUAUAUACCAUGAUCUACAGGAACUUGGUAGUAGUCAAUCAGCAGGAAUCAUCGGACUCAGGUACAUCUGUGAGUGAGAACAGGUGUCACCUUGAAGGUGGGAGUGAUCAAAAGGACCUUGUACAAGAGCUUCAGGAAGAGAAACCUUCAUCUUCACAUUUGGUUUCUAGACCAUCUACCUCAUCUAGAAGGAGAGCAAUUAGUGAGACAGAAGAAAAUUCAGAUGAAUUAUCUGGUGAACGACAAAGAAAACGCCACAAAUCUGAUAGUAUUUCCCUUUCCUUUGAUGAAAGCCUGGCUCUGUGUGUAAUAAGGGAGAUAUGUUGUGAAAGAAGCAGUAGCAGUGAAUCUACAGGGACGCCAUCGAAUCCGGAUCUUGAUGCUGGUGUAUAUCAAGUUACUGUGUAUCAGGCAGGGGAGAGUGAUACAGAUUCAUUUGAAGAAGAUCCUGAAAUUUCCUUAGCUGACUAUUGGAAAUGCACUUCAUGCAAUGAAAUGAAUCCCCCCCUUCCAUCACAUUGCAACAGAUGUUGGGCCCUUCGUGAGAAUUGGCUUCCUGAAGAUAAAGGGAAAGAUAAAGGGGAAAUCUCUGAGAAAGCCAAACUGGAAAACUCAACACAAGCUGAAGAGGGCUUUGAUGUUCCUGAUUGUAAAAAAACUAUAGUGAAUGAUUCCAGAGAGUCAUGUGUUGAGGAAAAUGAUGAUAAAAUUACACAAGCUUCACAAUCACAAGAAAGUGAAGACUAUUCUCAGCCAUCAACUUCUAGUAGCAUUAUUUAUAGCAGCCAAGAAGAUGUGAAAGAGUUUGAAAGGGAAGAAACCCAAGACAAAGAAGAGAGUGUGGAAUCUAGUUUGCCCCUUAAUGCCAUUGAACCUUGUGUGAUUUGUCAAGGUCGACCUAAAAAUGGUUGCAUUGUCCAUGGCAAAACAGGACAUCUUAUGGCCUGCUUUACAUGUGCAAAGAAGCUAAAGAAAAGGAAUAAGCCCUGCCCAGUAUGUAGACAACCAAUUCAAAUGAUUGUGCUAACUUAUUUCCCCUAGUUGACCUGUCUAUAAGAGAAUUAUAUAUUUCUAACUAUAUAACCCUAGGAAUUUAGACAACCUGAAAUUUAUUCACAUAUAUCAAAGUGAGAAAAUGCCUCAAUUCACAUAGAUUUCUUCUCUUUAGUAUAAUUGACCUACUUUGGUAGUGGAAUAGUGAAUACUUACUAUAAUUUGACUUGAAUAUGUAGCUCAUCCUUUACACCAACUCCUAAUUUUAAAUAAUUUCUACUCUGUCUUAAAUGAGAAGUACUUGGUUUUUUUUUUUCUUAAAUAUGUAUAUGACAUUUAAAUGUAACUUAUUAUUUUUUUUGAGACCGAGUCUUGCUCUGUUACCCAGGCUGGAGUGCAGUGGCGUGAUCUUGGCUCACUGCAAGCUCUGCCUCCCGGGUUCGCACCAUUCUCCUGCCUCAGCCUCCCAAUUAGCUUGGCCUACAGUCAUCUGCCACCACACCUGGCUAAUUUUUUGUACUUUUAGUAGAGACAGGGUUUCACCGUGUUAGCCAGGAUGGUCUCGAUCUCCUGACCUCGUGAUCCGCCCACCUCGGCCUCCCAAAGUGCUGGGAUUACAGGCAUGAGCCACCGCGUCCGGCCUAAAUGUCACUUAGUACCUUUGAUAUAAAGAGAAAAUGUGUGAAAGAUUUAGUUUUUUGUUUUUUUGUUUGUUUGUUUGUUUGUUUGUUUUGAGAUGAGUCUCUCUGUCGCCCAGGCUGGAGUGCAGUGUCAUGAUCUAGCAGUCUCCGCUUCCCGGGUUCAAGCCAUUCUCCUGGCUCAGCCUCUGGAGCAGCUGGGAUUACAGGCAUGCACCACCAUGCCCAGCUAAUUUUUGUAUUUUUAGUAGAGAUAGGGUUUCACCAUGUUGGCCAGGCUGGUCACGAACUCCUGACCUCAAGUGAGGUCACCCGCCUCGGCCUCCCGAAGUGCUGGGAUUGCAGAUGUGAGCCACCAUGUCCAGCCAAGAAUUAGUAUUUAAAUUUUAGAUACUCUUUUUUUUUUUUUUUUUUUUUUUUUUUGAGACAGAGUCUUGCUCCAUCACCCAUGCUAGAGUGCAGUGGAGUGAUCUCGGCUCACUGCAACUUCCGCCUUCUGGGUUCAAGCUAUUCUCCUGCCUCAGCCUUCCAAGUAACUGGGAUUACAGGCAUGUACCACCAUACCAGCUGAUUUUUUUGUAUUUUUAGUAAAGACAGGGUUUCACCAUGUUAGCCAGGCUGAUCUUGAACUCCUAAACUCAAGUGAUCUACUCACCUCAGCCUCCCAAAAUGCUGGGAUUACAGAUGUGAGGCACCUGGCCUCAGAUUUUUGAUACUCUUAAACCUUCUGAUCCUUAGUUUCUCUCUCCAAAAUACUCUUUCUAGGUUAAAAAAAAAAAGGCUCUUAUAUUUGGUGCUAUGUAAAUGAAAAUGUUUUUUAGGUUUUCUUGAUUUAACAAUAGAGACAGGGUCUCCCUGUGUUGCCCAGGCUGGUCUCGAACUCCUGGGCUCAAGAGAUCCUCCUGUCUUGGCCUCGCAAAGUGCUAAGUAGGAUUACAGGCGUUAGCCACCACACCCGGCUGUAAAAAUGUACUUAUUCUCCAGCCUCUUUUGUAUAAACCAUAGUAAGGGAUGGGAGUAAUGAUGUUAUCUGUGAAAAUAGCCACCAUUUACCCGUAAGACAAAACUUGUUAAAGCCUCCUGAGUCUAACCUAGAUUACAUCAGGCCCUUUUUCACACACAAAAAAAUCCUUUAUGGGAUUUAAUGGAAUCUGUUGUUUCCCCCUAAGUUGAAAAACAACUCUAAGACACUUUAAAGUACCUUCUUGGCCUGGGUUACAUGGUUCCCAGCCUAGGUUUCAGACUUUUGCUUAAGGCCAGUUUUAGAAACCCGUGAAUUCAGAAAAGUUAAUUCAGAAAUUUGAUAAACAGAAUUGUUAUUUAAAAACUAACUGGAAAGAUUGUUAAGUUCUUUCUGAAUUAUUCAGAAAUUAUGCAUCAUUUUCCUUCAAGAAUGACAGGGUCAGCAUGUGGAAUUCCAAGAUACCUCUUGACUUCCUCUCAAGCUCCGUGUUUGGUCAGUGGAGGCCCAUCCGAGCUCAGCACUGAGAAGUGUUAGUUUCUUUGGGACCCAUCUACCCUGACCACAUCAUGAUGUUCAUCUGCAGCUGUUGCAAGGUGUUCAGAUUGUAUAAACAUAAAUGUCACAAAAACUUUAAAAGAAGUGCAAUUCUCAAAAGGUUAGGUGGACUAAAGCAUUCUGUAAAGCAACUGCUAAUAAUGAGCUUACAGUGGAUUUGAAUUUGAAAAAUAUAGUAACAAGCCUGUCAAAUAUCUGCAAGAACUAUGGAAUAAAACUACUGAUGCAGUGAAGACAGUUGAAAAGAUCAAACAAAUGCCAAGCUAUAUUUAUAAUGAACAAAUUCAAGAAAAAGGACUACGGAAAGUUCAGGACAUCAAAGAAGUCAGGCAAAACUCAUCUUGACCCCUGUUGCAGGCAAAGGAACGCAGCUGGAAGAAAAGAUGAUAUAACAGUUAACAGGAUGCAGACAUGGCAGAGGUUUCCUAAAAAUCUCAUUAUCUAUAACCAUUUCUAUAUUUACAUUUGAAAAUCUCCUUUGGAGACUUAGAACCUCUAAAUUAUUGACUUAUUUUUUAUAUAAGGUCACUCCGAUGAAAGGUGAUUACAAAAUCAUCUACAUUGCUGUCUACAAAACAGAUAAUAUGGAUGUUUGAUCGCAUCUCAUUGUUAACUCUUUACUGAUAUGUUUGUAAAUACAGAAGUGAAAUGUGGACAUAAAAUAGUUACGCUAUUUGGUUAAUGGUACUAGACAACAUGUAAUUAAUGACAUUCAAAAAUUUAUGGCUAGUGAUAUAUAUAAAGUAAAAUUUUCUUUGCAGUAAAAUAUGCCCUUUAUUAUAGAAGGGAGGAUAUAAGGAACCAACAGUUUGUAUGAAAAUAGCUCAAAUAAUAUCUUUUAUUUUGAUUUUAAUAUUUCUUAUUUUGGUUUAUUAGUGUCUUAGAACAAAAUGGCCUUAUAUAAUGAAGCCUAGUUAUGCUGGACUGUUUUGAUCUCUUUUAAUUGUUCUGACAGAUAGUUGGGGAUGAGAGCCGAAUAAGGUUUGCCUGAAAUAACUGACACUAUAUAAUUUCUGCUUUGGCAAAUACUAAGUUCUAACUUGUCAUUCCUGGUAGAACAAGCUUUAUUUUUCGAGCCUAGCAAUGAUCUAGAAGCAGAUGUUAUCUCAGUGCCUUUUGCAAUUUGUUGUGUGGGUUUUUUUUUUUUUAAAGCCACACAAUAAUUUUGGAAAACAAUGUAUGGGUAGAACAUGUGUCUGUUAAUUGCACACAAAACCACUUUUAAUGGGUACAGAGUUAAAUUUGAAGGAAUAAGUUCUAGCUGAAGUAUUAUGAACUCCAAAUAAUGCUUUGAGGACCUCCAAAGGUAAAAGUACUAAUCCCUUUGGCCAUUUAUUGAGAGAGAGAGAGAGAGAGAGUAGGGUGACUAUAGUUAAUGUAUUGAAUGUUCUUGCUACAAAUAAAUGAUAUUUGAGCUGAUGGGUGUGCUAAUUACACUGAUUUGAUCAAUACCCAUUGUAUGUGAAACAGUACAUACACCAUAUUUACAAUUAUGUAUUUAACAUUUAAAAUUUCUAAUAUAAGUAUCUCUCAAACUGUGGAUUAACUUCUUGAUUUAUAUUUAAAUAUGAAUCUUAAGCAAAACAGUGAAAAUAACCAUCUUGAUUUAGUGUUUUUCUCCCAUAUGUGAAUUGUAUAUACUUAGGUGAAGACAAUAAAAUCAACUGAACUGUAAGCUUAGAAUAGGACUGAGGUAAUUCUGCACAGCAACUUUACUAAUGGUACAUUGUUGCUUCAAAACUCUCUCUCUCUCUCUCUGUCUGUCUCAAUAAAUGGCCAAAGGGAUUAGUAGUUUACCUGUGGAGGUCCUCCAAGCAUUAUUUGGAGUUGAUAAUACUUCAGCUACAACCAAGCAGAAUCUCUUUUUUUUGGAGGUCCUCGAAGCAUUAUUUGGAGUUGAUAAUACUUCAGCUUCAAUUUGGAGUUGAUAAUAUUUCAGCUAGAACCUAGUAGAAUCUGUUUUUUUCCUUUGGAGGUCCUCAAAGCAUUAUUGGAGUUCAUAAUACUGAAGCUAGAACCAAGCAGAAUCUGUUUUUUUCUGAGGAGUAUCGGUAGCAUAAAUGUGAUUAUAAACAUAGUACACUUGAUAUAUGGAGGCAGUGACAGCUAUUUUUACAAAAUUUAAAUCUGCAAAUGGAUUCAACAUGUUUAUGGGUUAUUAAAAUUGUCUGAUUUCUUAGGUUCUUUAUAGUACACGUGUUGAAAAUAAAUGAUUAAGAAUUGUUUCAAGAAUGCAAUUAUUUGAUCUUAAAUUUUUAUGAGUUGUUAAAAUAGAAAUUAUUUGAAUAUCAUAUAUUUGGGUAACAAAAGGCACAAGUCUGAAUGUGUUUCUUUUUCUGGAAUGGCCAUGCCUGCCCACUUUAGAAAUACAAAUAUCACUGGGCAGCUUGAAGCAGUUGGGAGCCUCCAAUGAGAGCAACUUGAGAGAAUGAUGUUGCAAGUUAGUAGGAGUAAGAAAUGCUGUGUUCUCCCUGUCUUCUCUUAGGUCACAUGGCAGCCUGGCCUAAGUGAUCGUGAAUGGUCUAUAAGGGAGGUAGCUGGGACAGGGAGGGGAGUUUGGGCUAGCCACCGUACCACUUGUCAGCGUGAAAAGUAAGAUUGUAAUUGCCUGUUUAGUUUUCUGCCUCAUCUUUGAAAGUUCCACCAAGCUGGGAACCUCUUGAUUGUGAGGCACAAAUGUAAGUACAUCAGAAAAAAACAAAAAAACUGGCUUUAAAGCAGGAGCUUGUGGGCCCCUAAGCCAGACGGGGACUAGCUUUUGGCAUUAUAUAAUUAAGAUUUUUUAAAUCCUUAAUAAGGGUUUUAUUUUAUUUUUAUUUAUUUUUUGAGACGGAGUCUUGCUCUGUGGCUCAGGCUGGAGUACAGUGGUGCAAUCUUGGCUCACUGCAACCUCUGCCUCCUGGCUGUGUUCAAGUGGUUCUGCUUCAGCCUCCCAAGUAGCUGGGGUUAGAGCACCCUGUCACCACGCCCCGCUAAUUUUUGUAUUUCUAGCAGAGAUGAAGUUUCACUAUGUUGGCCAGGCUGGGCUCAAACUCCUGACCUCAAGUGAUCUGCCCGCCUUGGCCCCCCAAAGUGCUGUGAUUACAGGCGUGAGCCGCCACGCCCAGCCUAAUAAGGGUUUUAAAGAUAAUUAGUGUGUAGGUCUGUAGGCUUAUGAUGGUAACCACAAGUUGUUAAUGGCAUUGUGAAAAGUUUUUAGUUGCGCUUUAUGGGUGGAUGCUGAAUUACAUUUUGAUUUGAUACUUAUAAAAAGAAAAAGUAUUUCUUCAGCUUAAAAAAUUGUUUAAAAGUUUGUGAUCAUAUUGUCUACCAUGUAGCCAGCUUUCAAUUAUAUGUAAGAGGGACUUUUUGACAUUUACAAAUAAUACUUUGAGGUAGAUAUCUGAAAGCACCAGCACUUGGAAGGUGUUCAGAAGUAACAAAUUAUAAAAUGAGCUAACAAACGAAAGGCAAAAUAAAACCGUAAAGCAAGCAGAUGGGAGGCGUGUUCAGUAACUUAUUCAUAAUGCAUCUGAAAUGAUUGCUGUACUCAAAUAUUUAACGUUAGAGUAAUAGUAUUUUGAAUGAAAACCAUAGUUGAUUGUCUUUAGAGAGAGGAGUGGUACUGAAACAUACUUGAAUUCGUAUUGCUUUCCUUUAAAGCUCUCCUUUAAAGACUUUAAAAAAAAUUCGAUAGGCAUUUUCAUGUUUCAGUCCUACAAUCCCACAUCUCUGCUGCCUUCAGAAUGCUACAACUUAGAUGUCCAGCCAACAGCUUAAAGCCAAUUUAUAAAAAUAGCAUCUUUCCUAAUUCCAAAAUUUCACCUUUUGUUUGUUUUGUUUUGAGAUGCGGUCUUGCUCUGUCGCCCAGGCUGGAAUGCAGUGCUGCAAACAUGACUCACUACAGCCUCAACCUCCUGGGCUCAAGCAAUCCUCCCACCUCAGCCUCCCAAGUAGCUGGGGACCACAGGUGCAAGCCACCAGGUCCAGCUAACCUUCCCCCCACCUCCCCCGACCCCGCUGCCACCCGCCCUGAGACAGAGUCUUGCUCUUUCACCCAGACUGGAGUGCAGUGGUGCAAUCUCGGCUCAUUGCAACCUCCACCUCCCAGGUUCAAGCAAUUCUGCCUCAGCCUCCUGAGUAGCUGGAAUUAUAGGUGCUCGCCAACCACACCUGGCUAAUUUUUUUUGUAUUUUUAGUAGAGAUGGGGUUUCAGCAUGUUGUCCAGGCUGGUCUCGAACUCCUGACCUCAUGAUCCGCCCACCUCGGCCUCCCAAAGUACUGGGAUUACAGGCGUGAGCCACCGUGCCCGGCCUAAUUUUUGUAUUUUUUGUAGAGACAGUUUCACCAUGUUGCCCAGGCUGGUCUCAAACUCCUGGGGUCAAGUGAUCUGCCCGUCUUGGCUUCCCAAAGUGCUGAGAUUACAGGUGUAAGCCACCACGCCAAGCCCAAAAUUUCACCUUUUAAAUUUAUUCCAUUUAUUUUGUAGGUGAAUUUCAUUUAUUUCUCAGGGUUAAAUUUUAGCGCUUUUGCCUGUGUCUAUUUUUGGUUCACACCUCCCCAGCCCACUGUCCUGUAUUAAGUAGGCCUUCCUUCAAGAUCACAGUAAUAUCUCCCUAAAUGGAUUUCACUACGUUUGGUCCUAUUUUUGGUUCAGUUAUAGUUUACAGAUACCAUCAUGUUGCUUCCCUGAUUUAAAUAUUGGGGGAAAAACUUGCUUUUUGGAUUUUAUCUCUGAUGUUCUACUGGAUUAUUUUAGACUUUUAGAACACUAUGAAAUGGGUGCUUGCUUUUCACUUUUCAAACCUUUUUUGCUUAAACAAAGUUCAUAAGCUUAUUGUAGUGGGAAGUUCAAAGUCACAGAUCUGGUACUUACUCGCCUAGUGACCUUAGAGACAAUAAAUCUAUAGAGCCUAGUAUGGGGUCUGGCAGGUAGUAAGCACUUUUAAUGAAUGGAAGUUUAAUAUUCUGUUUGCAUCCACUCGACCAUAAUCACCCCAAAUCCAGCUUAGGUAGCCUUGAAUUAACCCCUACUCCACCUUGAAGUUUUUUAUUUGUUUUUUGCUGAGACAGGGUCUCAUUCUGUCACCCAGGCUGGAGUAUAGUGGCGCAAACAUGACUCACUGCAGCCUCCUGAGUAGCUGGGAACACAGGCCUGUUGCCACCAUGCCUGGCUAAUAUAUAUAUUAUAUAUAAUAUACAUAUAUUACAUAUAUAUAUAUAAUACAUAUGUGUUUAUGUAUGUAUGUGUGUGUACAUUAUAUAUAUAUAUAUACUUUUUUUAGAGGCAGAGUCCUGCUAUGUUGCCCAGGCUGGCCUUGAACUCCUGGGCUCAAGCAAUCCUCGUGUCUUGACCUUGACCUCUCAAAAUGCUGGGAUUACAGGUGCGAGCCACUGCAUCUGGUGAAUUAAGCCUUUUUUAUACACUCAACUCUGAGGUAUUCUGUUCAUACCAAUAUGUUCCUUUGUAUCUUCUUGCCAUAGCAGGUUGUAACAUCCUUUUGUAUCUCCUUUCUUUUUUUUUUUUUUUUUUUGAGACGGAGUCCCGCUGUUUAGCCCAGGCCGGAUUGCAGUGGCGCAAUCUCGGCUCACUGCAAGCUCCGCCUCCCAGGUUCACGCCAUUCUCCUGCCUCAGCCUCCCGAGUAGCUGGGACUACAGGCGCCCGCCACCGCGCCUGGCUAAUUUUUUGUAUUUUUAGUAGAGACGGGGUUUCACCGUGUUAGCCAAGAUGGUCUCGAUCUCCUGACCUUGUGAUCCGCCCGCCUCGGCCUCCCAAAGUGCUGGGAUUACAGGCGUGAGCCACCGCGCCCAGCCGUAUCUCCUUUCAAAUGUCAAAUAAAUACAUUGUGUAUACAGUAGUAAAGGAUGUUGAUUGGCAUUGAAAGCAACUAUCAAGUUCUUGUUGAUUUAGAAGACAAAAAGACAAUUUUAAAAUAACAUCCUGGGCCAGGCUCUGUGACUCACGCCUGUAAUCUCAACACUUUGGGAGGCCAAGGAAGGAGGAUCACUUGAGGCCAGGAGUUUGAGAUCAGCCUGGGCAACAUAAUGACACCCUGUAUCCAAAAAAUUGUGGUGGCAUGCAUGGGAGACUGAGGUGGGAGGAUCACUUGAGCCCAGGAGUCCAAUGUUACAAUGAGCUAUGAUUGCGCCACUACACUCUGCUUAGGAGACAGAUGGAGACUUGUCUCUUAAAAAAAUAAAAAAUAACAGUAUGUUCAUUAAACAUUAAUCUCACUGAUUGUGAUUUUUUGUUUGUUUUUUUGAGAUGGCGUCUUGCUCUGUUGCCCAGGGUGGAGUGCAAUGGCGUGAUCUUGGCUCACUGCAGCCUCCACCUCCUGGGUUCAAGUGAUUCUCCUGCUUUAGCCUCCCAAGUAGCUGUGUUAUUUCAGCUAAUUUUUUCAUUUUUAGUGGAGAUGGGGUUUUGCCAUGUUGGCCAGGCUGGUCUCGAAUUCCUGACCUCAUGUGGUCCACCUGCCUCGGCCUCCCAAAGUGCUGGGAUUACAGGCAUUGAGCCACUGUGCCUGGCCUGAUUAUGAUUUUUUAAAGUCCCCCCCCAAAUUAUUGUUUGUGCAAUAAAUGGCAAAAAAGAAGCAUUCUAAGAAAAAAGUAGUCUUAAAAGUUGAUAUGGUGUCAGAAUUGUAAGAGAGAGGGUCUUGGCUGAAAAGCCUUUUUAGAAAAAAUUGCUCCCUACAAAAAAGGCCUUUUCUACCUUUUCUCACAUUUGUUUCUUUUUAUAGGAGGCAUCUGAGAAGACCAAAUCUCUUCAAAGUUAAGCUUUUUGUUUUUUUGGGGGGGACGAAGUCUCGUUCUGUCACCCAGGCUGGAGUGUAGUGGCAUGAUCUCGGCUCACUGCAACCUCUGCCUCCUGGGUUCAAGCAAUUCUCCUGCCUCAGCCUCCCGAGUAGCUGGAAAUUCAGGCGCCUGCCACCAUGCCCAGCUAAUUUUUGUAUUUUUAAUAGAGGCAGGGUUUCACUAUAUUGGCCAGGCUGGUCUCGAACUCCUGACCUCAUGAUCCGCCUGCCUCUGCCUCCCAAAGUGUUGGGAUUACAGGCAUGAGCCACCGCACCCAGCCCAAAGUUAAGCAUUUUUUAACCACAAGGUGGGAGGUGGAAGUAUCUCGUUGGAAGACUAAAGGUGUCCACUAACGGUAGACCCUUUUUUUUUUUUUUUUGAGAUGGAGUUUCACUGUCGCCCAGACUAGACUGAAGUGGCGCGAUCUCGGCUCACUGCAACCUCUGCCCCCCAGGUUCAAGUGAUUCUCCUGCCUCAGCCUCUAGAGUAGCUAGGAUUACAGGGGUCCACCACCACACCUGGCUAGUUUUUGUAUUUUCAGUAGAGACGGGGUUUCACCAUGUUGGCCAGGCUGGUCUCGAACUCCUGACCUCAGGUGACCCACCUGCUUUGGCCUCCCAAAGUGCUGGGAUUACAGGUGUGAGCCACUGCGCCUGGCCGUUUUUUUUUUUGUUGUUGUUGUUGUUUGUUCGUUUGUUUGUUUUGAGACAGUCUCUCACUCCAGGUUGGAGUGCAGUGGCACUAUCUCAGCUCACUGCAAACUCUGCCUCCCAAGGUCAAAUGAUUCUCCUGCCUCAGCCUCCCAGUAGUUGGAAUUACAGGCGCAUGCCACCAUGCAUGGCUAAUUUUUUGUAUUUUUAGUAGAGACGGGGUUUCACCAUGCUAGCCUUGAACUCCUGACCUUGUGAUCUGCCUGCCUCGGCCUCCCAAAGUGCUGGGAUUACAGACAUGAGCCACCAUGCUAGCCUUGAACUCCUGACCUCGUGAUCUGCCUGCCUCGGCCUCCCAAAGUGCUGGGAUUACAGACAUGAGCCACCAUGCCUGGCAAAUUUUUGUAUUUUCAGUAGAGAUGGGGUUUUGCUAUGUUAGCCAGGCUAGUCUCGAACUCCUGACCUCAGGUGAUCCAGUCGCCUCGGCCUCCCAAAGUGCUGGGAUUACAGAUGUGAGUCACUACGCUUGGUAGACUCUUAACAGCGCUGAGAGACCACUCCAAGAGAGCAGAGAAAUAAUAGUUCUAUUCUCAGUUGUCAAACAGCAAACAAAAAACCCUUGGCUGGGGGGUGAUGGCUCACCCCUGUAAUCCCAGCACUUUGGGAGGCUGAGGUGGGUGGAUCACUUGAGGCCAGGAAUUCAAGACCAACCUGGGCAACAUGGUGCAACCCUGUCUUAACUAAAAAUACAAAAAUUAGCCAGGCGUCAUGGCAUGUGCCUGUUAAUUCCAGCUGCUCGAGAGGCUGAGGCAUGAGAAUUACUUGAACCUGGGAGGUGGAGGUUGCAGUGAGCCGAGAUCCCACCACUGCACUCCAGCCUGGGUGACAGAGCGAGACUUCGUCCCAAAAAAAAAAAAAAAAGCUGCAAAUUUAAACGUUGAAGUCUAGGUAAAUAUACCAGGGAACUUCUGCUUAAGAGGCUUCUAUGUAAUGAAAUUCUCUUGAAAACAGAGAAACUAUUUCCUGUUUAUUUUCUAAAUUGAGACGUCACUUUUUAAAAAUUGGUACCUGUAAUUUAGCCAUUUCCUACUCAGCAAUGUCUCAUUUAAACUAUUAUUUGUUUAGCGUGUUUCAAAGAGCAGAUGUAAGCUUGAGCCCAUCCUCUGUCCUAUGACUAAGUCGAUAUUAGCAGGGGUUAGGACUGUUAGUUUUCCAGUUCCUACUGGAGGCAAAUUCUUUGUUUACCACUGUUCUCUGUAUUUCAAAAGCACCUGGAAAUCAAUAAAAUUUGUUAUUCAGAACAAAA